GGUAAAAUGGUUCAUCUGCAUACAAAGUUCAUGCAUGCUGUUAGCCAUGACUUUAGACUGUGCAGAAGGGCAGCUGUGAGGGACCCUUGAGGUCUAGUUCCCAAGGCUGUCUACCUCACAGCACUAGGGAAACUAUAAAGUGCAGAUCCCCAGGCCCCUUCUCAGACUUAGUGAACUGGAAUCUUCAGGGCUGGGGCCCAAGAAUCUGGAUUUUUAAAAAAUCUUCCCAGGUGAUUCUGAUGCACAGCUAGGUUUGGGAGCCACUGCUCCAAUCCUCGCCACUCAAAGUGAGCUUCAUUGGUCAGCAGCAUCGGCGUCACUUGGGAGUAUAAGUGCAGACCUGCUCACGCAGAUUCUGCAUUUUAACAGGACCCAUCCCUCCACCCCCCAGGGGAUUAGUAUGCAAUUCAAAAUUGGGAAUCACUGUUCUUUUGUUCAGGAGCUUCUGGGACAUUCUGCGCCCUCUCCCAACCUCAGCUGAGAUGGACAGCAAUCAUUAUCAGCUGUCCAUAGGUCUGUCCCCUAGGCCCUAAGGACUUUCUGCAGAAAGUCUCCAACCCUUAGAACCGCUUUUUUGUACCCCCGCAGUCACUUGUACACAUGGGAUGUAAAUGUUAAGGUUUAGACUGGUUUGGUUGUGGACCCACUUGGAGGCAGUGAAAGGUACUAGAUAACCUUUUGGGCGAUGCAGUUGGGCAGAUAAAGGUUAGACUUUGGGAAGAACAUCCUAGCUGUCUAUACCACACAAAGGGGAAAAGGCUAGAGUAUCUUCUUGGGAAGGUACAUUAGAGUCACACUCUCCUCACCUGGCCUGGGGGCAGGAGAAAGUGUAUGACGAUCUCACUCUGAUCCCAUCAUGACGUUUUCUGGGAGUAUCCUCAGAGAAUCCCAGAGAGGUAAGAGAAGGCUCAGGCUGCAGCCAGGAAGAGUGGAGCCAGCACCUGUGGCCUGCAGCAGCCUUCCACUGGCCACACCCCUGGAGCCUUUGCCUGCCCCCUCCUCCUCCCCAGCGCCUCAGCCAUCCUGAUGAGAGAAGAAGGGUCGGGGGCUGGGAAAGUGUGAUCUUUUUCGAGAGCGUGUGAGUAAUUUUCCAUCUGUUUAUGAGCUGUUGGAGCCCAGGUGUCUGCCAGCCACUCGCUGGAGGGUGAAAAUCCACACAGCAACCGGAAAAGGCGGCAAGCACACCAGGCUCCUUCCCUGGCCACCGGCUGAGGCUGCGUGGGUGGAGGCUGCCCUCCUAAGACCACAGGACCUUAGAAUACUGGGGCUGGAAGGCGUCAUGGAGGUCACUAAGUCCAACUGACUCUUUUACAGGCGCCUAGAUGCCAACCUCAUCUCCCUGGUCCCGGAGAGGAGCUUUGAGGGGCUGUCCUCCCUCCGCCACCUCUGGCUGGACGACAAUGCACUCACGGAGAUCCCUGUCAGGGCCCUCAACAACCUCCCUGCCCUGCAGGCCAUGACCCUGGCCCUCAACCGCAUCAGCCACAUCCCCGACUACGCGUUCCAGAAUCUCACCAGCCUUGUGGUGCUGCAUUUGCAUAACAACCGCAUCCAGCAUCUGGGGACCCACAGCUUCGAGGGGCUGCACAAUCUGGAGACACUAGACCUGAAUUAUAACAAGCUGCAGGAGUUCCCUGUGGCCAUCCGGACCCUGGGCAGACUGCAGGAACUGGGGUUCCAUAACAACAACAUCAAGGCCAUCCCAGAAAAGGCCUUCAUGGGGAACCCUCUGCUACAGACGAUACACUUUUAUGAUAACCCAAUCCAGUUUGUGGGAAGAUCGGCAUUCCAGUACCUGCCUAAACUCCACACACUAUCUCUGAAUGGUGCCAUGGACAUCCAGGAGUUUCCAGAUCUCAAAGGCACCACCAGCCUGGAGAUCCUGACCCUGACCCGCGCAGGCAUCCGGCUGCUCCCAUCGGGGAUGUGCCAACAGCUGCCCAGGCUCCGAGUCCUGGAACUGUCUCACAAUCAAAUUGAGGAGCUGCCCAGCCUGCACAGGUGUCAGAAAUUGGAGGAAAUCGGCCUCCAACACAACCGCAUCUGGGAAAUUGGAGCUGACACCUUCAGCCAGCUGAGCUCCCUGCAAGCCCUGGAUCUUAGCUGGAACGCCAUCCGGUCCAUCCACCCCGAGGCCUUCUCCACCCUGCACUCCCUGGUCAAGCUGGACCUGACAGACAACCAGCUGACCACACUGCCCCUGGCUGGACUUGGGGGCUUGAUGCAUCUGAAGCUCAAAGGGAACCUUGCUCUCUCCCAGGCCUUCUCCAAGGACAGUUUCCCAAAACUGAGGAUCCUGGAGGUGCCUUAUGCCUACCAGUGCUGUCCCUAUGGGAUGUGUGCCAGCUUCUUCAAGGCCUCUGGGCAGUGGGAGGCUGAAGACCUUCACCUUGAUGAUGAGGAGUCUUCAAAAAGGCCCCUGGGCCUCCUUGCCAGACAAGCAGAGAACCACUAUGACCAGGACCUGGAUGAGCUCCAGCUGGAGAUGGAGGACUCAAAGCCACACCCCAGUGUCCAGUGUAGCCCUACUCCAGGCCCCUUCAAGCCCUGUGAGUACCUCUUUGAAAGCUGGGGCAUCCGCCUGGCCGUGUGGGCCAUCGUGUUGCUCUCCGUGCUCUGCAAUGGACUGGUGCUGCUGACCGUGUUCGCUGGCGGGCCUGUCCCCCUGCCCCCGGUCAAGUUUGUGGUAGGUGCGAUUGCAGGCGCCAACACCUUGACUGGCAUUUCCUGUGGCCUUCUAGCCUCAGUCGAUGCCCUGACCUUUGGUCAGUUCUCUGAGUACGGAGCCCGCUGGGAGACGGGGCUAGGCUGCCGGGCCACUGGCUUCCUGGCAGUACUUGGGUCGGAGGCAUCGGUGCUGCUGCUCACUCUGGCCGCAGUGCAGUGCAGCGUCUCCGUCUCCUGUGUCCGGGCCUAUGGGAAGUCCCCCUCCCUGGGCAGCGUUCGAGCAGGGGUCCUAGGCUGCCUGGCACUGGCAGGGCUGGCCGCCGCGCUGCCCCUGGCCUCAGUGGGAGAAUACGGGGCCUCCCCACUCUGCCUGCCCUACGCGCCACCUGAGGGUCAGCCAGCAGCCCUGGGCUUCACCGUGGCCCUGGUGAUGAUGAACUCCUUCUGUUUCCUGGUCGUGGCCGGUGCCUACAUCAAACUGUACUGUGACCUGCCGCGGGGCGACUUUGAGGCCGUGUGGGACUGCGCCAUGGUGAGGCACGUGGCCUGGCUCAUCUUCGCAGACGGGCUCCUCUACUGUCCCGUGGCCUUCCUCAGCUUUGCCUCCAUGCUGGGCCUCUUCCCUGUCACGCCCGAGGCCGUCAAGUCUGUCCUGCUGGUGGUGCUGCCCCUGCCUGCCUGCCUCAACCCACUGCUGUACCUGCUCUUCAACCCCCACUUCCGGGAUGACCUUCGGCGGCUUCGGCCCCGCGCAGGGGACUCAGGGCCCCUAGCCUAUGCUGCGGCCGGGGAGCUGGAGAAGAGCUCCUGUGAUUCUACCCAGGCCCUGGUAGCCUUCUCUGAUGUGGAUCUCAUUCUGGAAGCUUCUGAAGCUGGGCGGCCCCCUGGGCUGGAGACCUAUGGCUUCCCCUCAGUGACCCUCAUCUCCUGUCAGCAGCCAGGGGCCCCCAGGCUGGAGGGCAGCCAUUGUGUAGAGCCAGAGGGGAACCACUUUGGGAACCCCCAACCCUCCAUGGAUGGAGAACUGCUGCUGAGGGCAGAGGGAUCUACGCCAGCAGGUGGAGGCUUGUCAGGGGGUGGCGGCUUUCAGCCCUCUGGCUUGGCCUUUGCUUCACACGUGUAAAUAUCCCUCCCCAUUCUUCUCUUCCCCUCUCUUCCCUUUCCUCUCUCCCCCUCGGUGAAUGAUGGCUGCUUCUAAAACAAAUACAACCAAAACUCAGCAGUGUGAUCUAUAGCAGGAUGGCCCAGUCCCUGGCUCCACUGAUCACCUCUCUCCUGUGACCAUCACCAACGGGUGCCUCUUGGCCUGGCUUUCCCUUGGCCUUCCUCAGCUUCACCUUGAUACUGGGCCUCUUCCUUGUCAUGUCUGAAGCUGUGGACCAGAGACCUGGACUUUUGUCUGCUUAAGGGAAAUGAGGGAAGUAAAGACAGUGAAGGGGUGGAGGGUUGAUCAGGGCACAGUGGACAGGGAGACCUCACAGAGAAAGGCCUGGAAGGUGAUUUCCCGUGUGACUCAUGGAUAGGAUACAAAAUGUGUUCCAUGUACCAUUAAUCUUGACAUAUGCCAUGCAUAAAGACUUCCUAUUAAAAUAAGCUUUGGAAGAGAUUACACAUGAUGUCUUUUUCUUAGAGAUUCACAGUGCAUGUUAGUGUAAUAAAGAGAUAAGUCCUACAGUA